GAGCUGUGCCCCACGCUCCCGCUGCAACAGUCCCGGGCAUCGCAGCUGCCAGUCAAGGCUAGGAGGCGGUCGGGGACUCCGCCUCCUCCCGACCCGUAGGUCUGGGAGCGCAAGUCCUGUUGCAGUCUUGCAAAGUGUAAAGCUGUCAGCCGCAGAGCACGGAGGAAAGACGGAGAGAAUGGAAGAGCUCCUGUCCGGUGUGCCAGCAGCCCGGACUGGCGGUGAGCGCGAGGGAGGCUACUGAGAAGCCCGGCGACGGAGGAACGCAGGUCUGCUGCCAGGGAUUGAGGAGACUGAAGAAUGCUGAAGACAGGCUGAUGGGCUCAGCUGGUAGGCUCCACUAUCUCGCCAUGACUGCUGAAAAUCCCACUCCUGGAGACCUGGCUCCGGCCCCCCUCAUCACUUGCAAACUCUGCCUGUGUGAGCAGUCUCUGGACAAGAUGACCACACUCCAGGAAUGCCAGUGCAUCUUUUGCACAGCUUGCCUGAAACAGUACAUGCAGCUGGCAAUCCGAGAAGGAUGUGGGUCUCCCAUCACUUGCCCUGACAUGGUGUGCCUAAACCACGGGACCCUGCAGGAAGCUGAGAUUGCCUGUUUGGUACCUGUGGACCAGUUUCAACUUUAUCAGAGGUUAAAAUUUGAAAGAGAAGUUCAUCUGGACCCCUACCGAACAUGGUGUCCUGUUGCAGACUGUCAGACAGUGUGCCCUGUUGCCUCGAGUGACCCAGGACAGCCUGUGCUGGUGGAAUGCCCUUCUUGCCACCUGAAAUUCUGCUCGUGUUGCAAGGAUGCUUGGCAUGCAGAGGUCUCCUGUAGAGACAGUCAGCCUAUUGUCCUGCCAACAGAGCACCGAGCCCUCUUUGGGACAGAUGCAGAAGCCCCCAUUAAGCAGUGCCCAGUUUGCCGGGUUUAUAUCGAACGCAAUGAAGGCUGCGCUCAGAUGAUGUGCAAAAACUGCAAGCAUACAUUUUGCUGGUACUGCCUCCAGAACUUGGAUAAUGACAUUUUCCUCAGACAUUAUGACAAAGGGCCAUGCAGGAAUAAACUUGGCCACUCAAGAGCAUCAGUGAUGUGGAACCGAACACAGGUGGUGGGGAUUCUCGUAGGCUUGGGCAUCAUUGCCUUGGUUACUUCACCCUUGUUACUCCUGGCCUCCCCAUGUAUAAUCUGUUGUGUCUGCAAGUCCUGUCGGGGCAAGAAGAAAAAGCACGACCCAUCCACAACCUAAAGAUCUCUGUGUUCAUACGCCCCAGAUAUGUGAGUUACAUGAGAUGGCACAGUGAUAAAGCCCCAUUUAGUGACCUUGCCUCCUUCUCCUUGCCAACUUUGAAAGUGCCUCCGUGUCCAGACUUUGAACUUGCCUGCCAGCCUUCAGCAUCAGGAAAGGCCAAGUCCUGGGUGUGAGUGUUCCUGUGUAACAAGAACUGGGCUCAACGGUCCAGCUGUUUCUAUGGAGCUUUGGGGUUCCUUGAGAUGAAUGAACAUAUCAUUUUAUCAUCCAAAGGAUCUCACUGGACUGUUCAACUUCCAGCCAAAUUCAAGGAGCUUGCGGGAACAUUUGAUAUAACAAAUGUGUUGUCAUUGUUGGCAACAUACAAGAUAACCAAGAAGCUGGAGUCUGUUCUGUGUUGAUUUGACUGCCAUGAGAAACACAGGGGAAACCUGAUGAGGAGAAGGAUAAGACUGCGUAAGGAGAAAUCCUCAUAGGAGCUAUAAAGCAGGCUGCUGAUCUCAGCAGUUGAUAUGGUGGUUGUGCCUCUGCUGGCUACUGGGUGUGCUGUCCCCAUGUUCCCGCUGUGAUUUGGCAGAAACACAAUAGGCUUCUCCUUGUGUGAUCUCAGCUUCAAGCAGGUGAAACUGCUGUGCAGAGGGAGUUGCCCCUUCCCAGUAAAAGAGUUGCAGCCUGUUAAACAAUGUGGUCUAAUUUAGUGUCUCUCCCUUGGCAAAUGUAAGUUUUCUAAGUUGGCCAACUUGUCUCUUACAGCCAGUGGCUGUGGUCUACAGAAUUGUUUCAUAUAAAAUACGGGUAGAGUGGUAGAGUUUCAAAACUUUCGUCAUAGAUAUCUGGGACCUUUCUCAGGAUCUGUGUUCACACAGCCAAUAGAUUUGGAAUCAGGCCUAAGAGUACACAUGGAGGGUAAAUAUUAAAGUGCGUAUUAUGUACAUCUAGAAUCCAUGUGACUUGCAGCCUACCUGUAAUUUCUAUCCAUUGAGCAUGCAUGGAUAUACCCAAUAGUACACACAAAAUAAAUGUUUACUUAAGAGCCAUUCUAUCCUUUUGUGACUGAAAUGGUUUAUUGUAAAUCUGCCUAAAGAUUUUUUGCAUAUUAUAUAUGUGAAUUUUGGUUGUAAGUUCAUAACUUACCCAAGGGUAUAGACUCAUAACUCUUUUAAAACAGUGCUUAGUACAAUAUCCUGCCAUCUCUGUAAAAACGCUAAUUGAUAACCGAGUCAUUUACAUGUUUUCGAACACAGAAUAGCUCUUUUCUCAGCAUCAUUAUUGCUCUUUCAGCAUCUGUUAGGACAGUCUGAAUACUUUCUGUUUCAAGGCACUGAUAAAACCGCAACAAAAACAUGUAAGAAAUAAAAUAGAAAUGCUUUAUAUAAUUUAGUUUAAAUUUAUGUAUCACCUCAUUGUGACUUAUUUUUUCCAUUAUACCAUUAGUCAGAUUUGAAUAACGAGGUUUUGAAAGGAUAAAACCUUUUCUCCAAUGACAGGAUUAUAUAAUUGCUAUUGGCAAUGUAGCCUGGUGCUUCAUGAGACCUAUGCUAAAUGUUACUGGAGAGUUCUUGAAGCCAGGGAUACCAUAUCAGGAACUAUUCAGGAUCUAUGAUAUUUUCUGAGGUAACUGGGUAAUAGAAUAUCAAAUUGCUGCUAUCUCGGACCUAUUGUUAAAGGAUGAUGCUUUGCCUAUGUAAUAGGAUAUAUCCUAAGUGGGGAUGUGUAUAUUUCAGGAACUUUAAUUCACAAGUAUAUAUUGAUAUCUGAUGUGUGUAUAGUACAUCUGUUGGUUAUGUACAUUUUAAUUUACAUGUUGUGUAGAACAUAGAUGAGAACUCUGGGAAAACUUGGGAAUGGCAACCAACCAAAAUCAUUUUUAAUCAUUUAUUAGAAAUUUCUCAAUAUUGUGUCUUUUUCUUUUGAAACUCUAAACACUUCAGAAAAAAACACUAUCAGUGUAGUUCAUGUUAGUAUAAUUAUAGAUUUACAUAUAUUUGAAUAGUUAAUUUGCUUUGUUUUACACGUAGCCCACUGCCUCAUUAUAGGUAAAAGGCAUUUAUAACUGCUCAGGGGAUUACGAGAACUCAACUGAAACUGAAUUUUUGUAACAAGAAUGUUAAUAGUGGCAAAGUCCUCUGUCAGUAAACUCUUUAAGCUUGGUGCUGCAAAGAGUCUUUAAAUGGGGGCUGAUUUCAAGUAACCUAAAAGACUGUGUUAUCAGAGGAAGAGGUCCCAAAUUUGGAGUAAAGAUGGGAGAAAAUAAAUAUGUGCUAUUUCCUUGGCGAGUUGAGGGAAUUUGCCACCUUACAGAGUUUGUAUCACUGAAUUAGCUGCUUUUGUUUUUUUUUUUUUUUUUUUGCCAGGGCUAUGGAGUGGGGGUUGUUUGUCAAACUGAUUUUCAAUAAUUGGAUUUAAUUUUUUUUAACAUUGAAAAGUGCCUGAAAAAUGGUAAAUUCUUAAAUGUGUGUGAGAUUGUCAGAAUCAACAAAACUAGGUUGGUUAAACAUAUCUCUGGUACAUCAAGGGGCAUGAUACAAACCAGUCUAAAGACUGUUUAUAAAGGAGAGAGCUGGCGACUUAUUUUUAUUUUUAUUUUUUGGACAGAGUCUCCCUUUGUCACCCAGGCCGGAGUGCAGUGGCAUGAUCAUGGUUCACUUCAACCCCUACCUCCUGGGCUCAAGUGUUCCUCUCACCUUAUCCUCCUGAGCAGCUGGGACUACAGGCACACACCACCACACCUGGCUAAGUUUUGUAUUUUUUGUAGAGAUGGGGUUUCUCUGUGUUGCCCAGUCUUGUCUCAAACUCCUGGGCUCAAGCGAUCCACCCACCUUGGGCUCCCAAAGUGUUGGGAUUACAGGUGUGUGUCACUGUGCCUGACAGCUGACAGUUUUAACUGACAACUUUGAUAACAGAGGCUGCUAUUUUUGUUUUAGAUAAUUGGCCAGUGACAGAGUUUACCCUUGCCUCCUUUCUUGGUCUGCCAGCUUUGUCCUUUCUGAGUGAUUCUCUUUCUGUAUUGAGAGGAAGUGUGGGUCUACAUAGGGAUGUUUGGAUGCUAUGGCAAGAAUCUUUUUGUGUUUGGAGUGUAGUCCAUUUGCAAUAGAAAUAAAAAAAUCCGUCACCAAAUUGUAACCUGGAUGUUAUAGCCCAGCAUCUAGAAAUCCUAUGAAACGUAUUAGCACAAUAUCUUGCCAUUGUCCCAUCUAGGAAAUUUUUUCUUGUUGUGAGGUAGGGAAGUGAGGAGGAAAGCCAUGCCGAAGCAAAUGUUAGAAUCUUAGGCAUCCUAUUUGUUCAUGCCAUGGGUAUUUGCUUUGGACUUGGAGUCUGUACUUUGAAAGAGGCCUUUGAAAAACAAAUAAUUCUGUGUGAAUUUUCUUGUAGCGUGCUUCAUGAAAAUAUCUACUUAUCCAGGUUUGCAAAUGUACAUGUUCAUUUGAAUGUAAAUCACCAUUUCUUGGAACCCCACGUUUUUUCUUAAAAAUUAUUCUGAAUUAAAUGUAUAUUUCUUUAGCCUUCCCUACACAGUACUAAUAAAAGACUUUUCUUUCUGUUCAUGAAUGGAUGCCUUUAUGUGAUAUAGAGUCAUGUGUGUAUGUGUAGCUUUAAGGGCAAUUUCAGAAAUGCAUUAGAUGAAUGACAUUUUAUAAAGCGAUCACAAUUGAUAUCUACAGGCUAUUAUGUCUCAUGUUGAUUCAUGAUCCAGGAAGUUUUAUGUAUUUAAAAAAUUGCUAUCGUGUUAUAUUUUUCCAAUUUUUGGAGAAGAAAAUAGCUGUUUAGGCUCUCUAGCCACAAUAAAUGUAAGCAGGAAA